CUUCGCCAGCAUCUCCCCGCUGCCCUCAACACACACACACACACACACACACACACACACACACACACACACACACACACACACACACACACACGGCACCUGGGCUAGGCCCGGACACCUGUCUGCAGCAUGGAUAAGUAUGACGACCUGGGCCUGGAGGCCAGUAAAUUCAUCGAGGACCUGAACAUGUAUGAGGCCUCUAAGGAUGGGCUCUUCCGAGUGGACAAGGGUGCAGGCAACAACCCCGAGUUUGAGGAAACUCGCAGGGUGUUCGCCACCAAGAUGGCCAAAAUCCACCUCCAGCAGCAGCAGCAGCAGCUCCUGCAGGAGGAGACUCUGCCCAGGGGGAGUAGAGGCCCUGUCAAUGGAGGGGGCCGCCUGGGCCCACAGGCCCGUUGGGAAGUUGUGGGCAGCAAGCUGACUGUGGAUGGUGCUGCCAAGCCUCCUCUUGCUGCCUCGACAGGGGCACCUGGGGCAGUCACCACCCUCGCUGCUGGGCAGCCCCCGUACCCACCGCAGGAGCAGAGAUCCAGGCCAUACCUGCAUGGCACGAGGCAUGGCAGCCAGGACUGUGGUUCCAGGGAGAGCCUGGCGACUUCUGAGAUGUCUGCUUUCCACCAGCCAGGCCCCUGUGAGGAUCCUUCCUGCCUCACUCAUGGAGACUAUUAUGACAACCUCUCCUUGGCAAGCCCAAAGUGGGGUGACAAACCAGGAGUGUCCCCCAGCAUCGGCCUGAGUGUAGGGAGUGGGUGGCCUAGCUCCCCGGGGAGUGACCCACCACUGCCCAAACCCUGCGGGGACCAUCCCCUAAAUCACCGACAGCUCUCCCUGAGCUCCAGCAGGUCUUCUGAGGGUAGCCUCGGUGGUCAGAAUAGUGGCAUUGGUGGCCGCAGCAGCGAGAAGCCAACAGGCCUUUGGUCCACUGCCUCCUCCCAGCGGGUGAGCCCUGGCCUGCCUUCCCCAAACUUGGAGAACGGAGCACCAGCUGUGGGGCCUGUUCAGCCCAGGACCCCUUCUGUGUCAGCACCCUUGGCCCUGAGCUGCCCCAGGCAAGGAGGUCUUCCAAGAUCAAACUCGGGGCUGGGGGGUGAGGUUUCAGGUGUGAUGUCCAAACCCAAUGUGGACCCCCAACCCUGGUUCCAGGAUGGGCCCAAAUCUUACCUUUCCAGUUCUGCCCCGUCAUCCUCGCCAGCUGGUCUGGACGGUUCACAGCAGGGUGCGGUCCCUGGGCUGGGGCCGAAGCCUGGCUGCACAGACCUUGGCACUGGUCCCAAGCUCAGCCCCACCAGUCUUGUCCAUCCAGUGAUGUCCACCCUGCCUGAGUUAUCUUGUAAAGAGGGUCCCCUGGGCUGGUCUUCUGAUGGUAGCCUGGGAUCUGUGCUCCUGGACAGCCCCAGCUCCCCUAGGGUAAGGCUGCCCUGCCAGCCCCUCGUCCCAGGUCCUGAGCUGAGACCCUCUGCUGCUGAGUUGAAAUUAGAAGCCCUCACCCAACGUCUGGAGCGAGAGAUGGAUGCUCACCCGAAGGCUGAUUACUUUGGAGCCUGUGUGAAAUGCAGCAAAGGGGUGUUUGGGGCUGGCCAGGCCUGUCAGGCCAUGGGGAACCUCUACCAUGACACAUGCUUCACCUGUGCAGCUUGCAGCCGGAAGCUGAGAGGAAAAGCCUUUUAUUUUGUCAACGGCAAAGUGUUUUGUGAAGAAGACUUCCUGUACUCUGGUUUCCAGCAGUCGGCUGACAGGUGUUUUCUUUGUGGACAUCUGAUCAUGGACAUGAUCCUGCAAGCCCUGGGGAAGUCCUACCACCCCGGCUGUUUCCGCUGUGUCAUCUGUAAUGAGUGUUUGGAUGGGGUGCCCUUCACCGUGGACUCAGAGAACAAGAUCUACUGUGUCCGAGAUUACCACAAGGUGCUGGCCCCCAAGUGUGCAGCCUGUGGGCUUCCCAUCCUUCCACCUGAGGGCUCAGAUGAGACCAUCCGUGUCGUGUCCAUGGACAGAGACUACCACGUGGAGUGUUACCACUGCGAGGACUGUGGUCUGGAGCUCAAUGAUGAAGAUGGCCACCGCUGUUAUCCGCUGGAGGACCACCUGUUCUGUCACUCCUGCCACGUGAAGAGGCUGGAGAAGAGACCCUCAUCUACAGCCCUUCACCAGCACCACUUCUAGCCAGAGCCACUUGCAGACAUCACGGCAGGGGAUGAGGAGCCGGGGUUGCUGCUGCUGCUUCCGGUGGCCCCUGGGGUGGAAGUGGGGUAGGGGAAGAGGAGGGGCAGGAGGGAGAGUUCCUGUGAGCAUGUGGGGGGUGCCUUUCCUUUAACCAGGGAGGUGAACACUACCUGCCUCCUGCGUGUAUUUUCCAAGUGCUUUUCUCUGUUGCCACAUUUUCCUCAGGUUACUCAGGAAAAUGCUCCAGCAUGUGCGAGCACAUGACCUGAGGUUGCAUCAUAGCACCAAAGGAAUCCUCCUGUCCCCUCUGGGAACAUUUCAUGCUUCAGAGGGAGAGGUUUUUAUUGAGCUUGUUUCACAAUAUCCCCUUGAAGGGACAGCUCAGCUGCCAAUACAUUCAACCCUUUCUCUUCCUUCAGGAAAAUACCUAUACCCAAAUGUUCCCUCCCCCGACAUAUAUCAUGGCAUGAUUUAAGGCUUCUUUUCACCUGAGAGCUUCAGUUCUUCUGCAGAAUGGCUGCAAAUUUAAUUGCAUUAAGGCAAGAAGGAAGCUCUAAUGUGUGCUUUGUAUCCUAAGAUAAAUUUGCUUAGAAAACCAGAGUCAAGAUUUGAAAUAGGUGAGGCAGGGUUUCCUCCUUAGACACUGACAGCAUUCUCUGUACCCCUUCAAAUCCUUACUCUCCUAAAGGCAGCUGAGUCCGCGACAGAAAUUUGCCCUAUGUGAGUAAAACAUACUUUGGGAGAAGAACUUGGUGCAGGCACCAGGAUUUUUUUUUUUGCCCACGUGUUUGCGCUGUUUUUCUCUGGAGUUCUCAAGAGUUGGUGACUUGGAAGGCCGCUUCUGCAAGGCAAGUCUCAGGAACCCAUGCAGGUACAUCGCUUGCACCUGUUUUUAGCUUAUUUAAUGACGGGCUUUUGGGAAGAGCUGCCCGCAUACUGAGAGACAGCUUCUUAUAAACAAGGAGAGUUUUUGUGUGUGCGAGAUCUCUAAGCCAGCGUGGGAGGGAGCGCCUCAGGAUAAGUUAUUAUAUUCAUUUCGUUGGUUUCUCUCCUGCCCAAUUCUUGGCACAGGCAUUAUGUUUGAAGAAACCAGGAUAAGGUACACUGCUUUUGUCUGUUUAAUUUUUUUAGUUGUUUCCCUUCACUUUCAGUCUUCCACACACAAAAAAUACCUCACAGAGCUUCACCAAAUCACAGAUUCAGGAGGAAUUUGGCUUUCACACUGGACUCAGAUACCUUCUUCAGUGUGUUGGAAAUCACUGGCUUCACACAGGCCCAACUCCAGCUGGUCAGGGCAGAGUGAUCGUAACUAAAGGUCAGUGGGGAAUAGAUCCGAUUCAGUGCUUUUGCCUUAUGCAUUUCAGCAUCCUGGCUCCCCAGGGUGGCAGGAGCUGAGGGAGGGCCACACACUGGCAAGAUUUCAAGACCACUCUCUGCACUGAAGAGGUAAAAUUUGCACUGCAAGUCACAUCCCUGAGGCCAGAGGUCAGUACCCUUUGGUAUUUCGAUUAGAAGAAGCUGCAAAAGAAAGGCAGCCCAUUUUACCAUUGCCAGCCAGGCCGGGGACACAGGAGCCGGUGUGUGCACUCUGCCUCCUCACCUUGCACCCAGAGCAAGAGGACUGGGUGCUGGGCUGCAGAGGCCGGUCAGUGGAGCCCCUAGCACGUGUGAACUCAGGCUUUUCAUUGGGCCCGGCUCCACUUCUAGGCCAUGUUUUGACUCAUUUGGUAACCAUUGCCUGUAAGCAGCACAGAAUUGGUGCCAUGGAUUAUCUUUUCCAUGUUGAUGGAAUUCAUUCUGUUGGAAUCCUUUGGCCAGAUGUCACUUCAGCCAGGGUGUGCAUCAUCAUUGGUUCUUUUUCACAGGCUGAGCCUCCUGAAAACCCAUGAACGCUGGGGCUGGGGAAGUGAACCCUGAGGUGGGGACCCUCUCUUCCCAUCAAAUCAUCCAGCUCAGUGUGGGGCGUGGCAGGGGGGUAAAUGAAGCCAGCCAAUGUGUUAACCUGUCUCUGUCAACCUAAGAAUGUUGGCCUUACUGACACACCUUUGCUCCAUGUUCAAGACCAGAAGUAGCUGGGAUUUGUUUGCAAAUUGGGUAAUUAGUUUAAAAAUCUGUGAUUACAUUUUUAAAUGAAAUUUUCAAAGUGGCCUAGAUUGAGGUGAUUCAGAUAGGUUUGCGAAUAUACCAUUUUAUAUUGUUGAGAAAGAACAAAAAGGGAAUUUCCAGAUGUCCUAGAAAUCCUAGCAACAGAUUUCUCUGGUUGUCAGUUUCCCUGGAGAAGGCGCCAGAUAGGAAUCUCCAAUCAGUUGUUUUUCUCUUCGCUUCAGGCCCUUACACAAAAGCCAUGAAGAGAUGUUCACCUACCCGGUAUUUUAAAUGUUCUGUAAAUUAUUAGCCAAAUAGAACUGUAAUGGGGUUGUAUUUAUGGGCGCCUAGAAAGAAAACACAAGGACUUGGUAGGCCAGGAAGAAAAGAUUUUAAAAUUUAGAAUGAAUAGCCCUUCUGGGUUUUCUUUUUGACAAUUCUUGGACUUGAGGUAAAACAAGGAGGAUUGUGGCCGGAUUUCAGAUCCCAAAGCCAGCCUCCAUCUUAGGCCUUUGCCUCAUUGUGCCUUUUAGGUUUUCUUACCCACCGUCUCCUGUUUUGUCUUUUUUUUCUUUUCUCCUACCCCUAUCUUGGGACAUUCAGAAACUGCCUGGGUGGUUUGAGAAGAGACAACCCAGUUUGAUCUGCAAUACAAGGAUCCAUUCGUAAUCUCUCUCUCACUGAUGUUAUUCCCCCAUCUGCCGUCUUGGUUCAUCUCACCACAGAAGGGCAUUUAGUCCUACCCAGCCAUCGGCUGCGUAUGACAGCAGGAUGGCACUUCCCAUUUCUCUGUGGUUAGUGCUCGAGUGAAAACCUCUUUCAGCUGAGUCCUCUGAGGUUCUGCUGUUGAGUCCUGGGUGGCUGAUGGAAUGAUUGAGGAGGUCUGGUCACCCUCAAGCGCCGUCAUCGCCUUGUUUCCAUGGGCUUCUGUCACACAAAAUGAAGAACAGAAAUGUUAGGACUUAAGAGAAUGUUUGGAAUUCACACCUCUUUGCAGUCCUUUCAAGGCUGCUGCUCUGUGCUGUGUCCCAUGCAUGUGAAAGUAGAGCUGUGAUGGCUGCUGGGACGCUUGCAAAGAUCAUGUGUGAGAAUUGAGCACAAGACCACAAAUUAUUACUGCUUGAUGCGCUUGUUAAAACUCUAUCUGCCAGGAAACCAAAUUUUCUUUUCUUUUCUUUUUUUUUUUGAGACAGGGCCUCACUCUGUUGCCCAGGCUGGAGUGCAGUGGCGCGAUCUCAGCUCACUGCAGCCUCCACCUACUGGGCUCAAGUGAUCCUCCCACCUCAGCCUCCCGAGUAGCCGGGACCACAGGCGUGUAUGACUGGCUACGCCUGGCUAAUUUUUGUAUUUUUAAUAGAGACGAGUUUCACCAUGUUGCCCAGGAUGGUCUGGAACUCCUGGGCUCAAGUGAUCUGCCCACUUCCGCCUCCCAAAGUGUUGGGAUUAUGGCCAUUAGCCACUGUACCUGGCACAAUUUUUUUUUGUACCCUCCUUUAUGCCAAGAAUCAGUCCUAAUUUCUUUACUAUGUGAAGUAACUUUUAAAGGUAAUAGAAAAGGCCAGGCACAGUGGCUCAUGCCUGUAAUCCCAGGCGCCGUGGCUCACGCCUGUAAUCCCAGCACUUUGAGAGGCUGAGGCGGGUGGAUCACUUAAGGUCAGGAGUUAGAGACCAGCCUGACCAACAUGGUGAAACACUGUCUCUACUAAAAAUACAAAAUUAGCUGGGUUUGGUGGCGCACGCCUGUAAUCCCAGCUACCUGAGAGGUUGAGGCAGGAGAAUCGCUUGAACCUGGGAGGCAGAGGUUGCAGUGAGCCGAGAUGGUGCCAUUGCACUCCGACCUGGGCAACAGAGCGAAACACUGUCUCAAAAAAAAAAAAAAAAGUAACAGAAAAAAGAGUGAAAUAUAUUAGCUAUCUUUUAUUCUGAGCCAAAACUUGACAGAUGUGGGAAAUCUUCAUAUAGUGUAUGAAAAUUUCAUUGUACAGGGAAAUUAUUUUCCUCUGUGUCUUUUCUUUUACUAUAAAGUGAUUCAGAAUUUUACUGUUACUAUAAAAUUAUGCAAAGUAUUGUGACAAAACUGCAUCAAUUUGUUGACUAUUAAAGUGCUCCUUGAACAUUAUAUUUCCUGGGUCUUUUCUGUGUGUGGAGUCAGCAAACUGUUUUUUGCUACCUGGACUUUGUCUUCUUUUACAGCUCUGGAUUCUUAAAAGUACCACAUAGGUAGCAAACCUGUGAAGGGUAUGAGAUUUUACCCUACUUGCAGGCUAAUAAAGUGAGCACACCACAUGGGUUCAUGGAUCCUGGCAGAAGUUAUGAGACUCAUAGGUCAGAGACAAAGGACAGUUUAUUAUAGCAAUAGCAGUGGCCAGAUUAUCAGCAUUUACACUGGUUCCCUGAGCCCCAGGCCCCAAGAAGAGGGCCAGGUGAGACCUGCACACGCAGUGGGCUGCAUUACAAGAGGAACCCCCAUGCUUAGGGGACCCUGGUAUUUGAUAAUGGGCAGUAAGCCUGCCUGACUUUUGCUCCAGAGACAGACACUAUCUCUGUCAUCCAAGACUGUUCACUAGAUAAACAUCCUUGAAAAUAUAAGUCUGGAACCUGGCAAUUGGUGUCUAUUCUUACCAGAUGUAUAAAAAUGUGAGAGGCCUUGGAGAAUCAUAUCCCAAGAAUCAGCAGUUUCUUUUACUGGACCUUUAAGAUUGAGACUUGUAAGGUCCUGAUGCAGUGACUUGUAAGGUCACUUUGUCUCUCUUGUGAAUGUUACUGUUUUUUCUCUUCUGAGGUUAUGACCAAAGAAUCCUCAAGGCGAGUGAUCCUUCAGGUUUGAGACAGCCACAUGCAGGAAGACAGGACUUGUAGAGUGUUGGGGCCAAGUGUGUGGUUAGAAUCCUUGGGGUGGGGAAAGAGUUUGUUCUAGACUCCAGUGUAGUCCUUGUGGCUACCAGGUCUGACGUGCCAAGGACACGGGAAAGCUGGGAGUGAGGAUACUCAUAGUCAUAGCACCUUACACCAGAAUAAAAGUUUUUUUUUUCUUUUUAAGUGAUGAGAGAAUGGCUAGUCUGAUUUUGCCAACAUGGGCUGCUAUUUGCUUAAGACCUUGAUGGUAUAAGGAGUGAAGAUGCAAUCAGGGUAAAAGGCGGUCUGGAGUUGUGGUGUGCUGGCAAACCAGCCCUCUGGGGCAAAAAAUUAAAAAGCCUUGAUAUGGAGUGUUUGCUGAUACCUAUGAUGUAAAUAUUCCCGCCAUGGCCACUUUCCAGCUACCAGCAAGGCAUCCUGGCACCAGGGAUUGGGAGGAGAUGGCAUAGUCCUAAGAGUCAGCCUUGGGCAUUGGGCCAUGUGGGACUGGGCAGUGGGGUAUCUGGUCUGGUUCUAAGUGCUGUGAUGAAGCAGUAGCAGCUGUAAUAGCUGGCAUUUCCCGUGUGCUCAUCACAUAGCAGAUGUUAUUCCAAGGACUGUAUGUUCUUUAUCAUCCCUCAUUUGAUAGACAAGACAACUGAGACACAAAAGGGUGAAAUAAACAGUAAGUACUCCAUCCCAGGCCAUCUCAUCCAGAGGGUGCUGUCUUGACCACUCUACUACUCUGGUUGAUGGGAGGCAGUAAAUUGUCCAUCAGUAUACUUCUUCAUCAAAGCUACAUAGUCAAAAAGCCACAGGAGGCUGUGAGGAGAAGCUCACUGCUGCUCUGUUGAAGUCUGUAUUGGUUUCCUAUGGCCACUCUUAACAAAUUACCACAACCUCAGUGGCUUAAAACAACACAAAUAUAUCAUUCUGUCAUCCUGGACACGAGCCAAAGGUUGUCGGCAGAAGCGAAUUGCUUCCAGAGGUGCUAUAGGGUGCUGCCCAUUCCUUGCCCCUUUUCCGCUUCUAGAGGCUGCCCAUUUUCCUUGGCUUGUGGCUGCAUCAUUCUGGCUGCUUCUAUUGUCACACCUCCUCUCUGACCCUCCCUGCCUCCUUGUAAGGACACUUGGGAUUACGCCCAUCCAGAUAAUCUAGAAUAAUCUCCCAUUUUGUGAUUCUUAAUAACAUCUGCAAAGCCUCUUUUACCUUGCAGAAUAAGAUAUUCACAGGUUCUGGUGAGGAGGACAGGGACAUCUCUGAAGGGGAGGGAAGCAGGAGAUAGGGUCUGGAGGCAUGGAAUUGGCUUCCUAAGGCCAAUUCAGGCUGACUUCCUAGAACUAAGUCAAAAGGAAAACCCCAACUUUCCACGCUCAAGUAACAAAAGGACCAGAGGCUACUCCCUUUGCAACCUCCCCACCCCCAGCCCCUUUUCUGCAUGGCAGGUGAAAAAUUGAAAGUAUCGCUAAUUGAUCCCCUCCCACAACCAAUCAGACUGGUCUUAGGCCAAGUCUUCAUUUGCCUAGGAGUAUAACUUUGUAACUUCAGCCUCUGAUUGGGCGUUUUACACAACCAGUCAGAUGUUUGUAUAGGGUGGUGUAACUUUGUAACUUUGCUUCAGCCUCUGAUUGGUCCCCUCCCACAACCAAUCAAACUGAUCAUGGACCUCUGCUUCAUUUACAUAGGGUGUACACCAAGUAACCAAUGGGAAACCUCUAGAGGGUAUUUAAAUCCCAGAAAAUUCUGUAACCGGGUUCUUGAGCUGCUUGGGCUGCUCCCACCCUGUGGAGCGUACUUUCGUUUUUCAAUAAAUCUCUUUUGUUGCUUCAUUCUUUACUUGCUUUGUGCGUUUUGUCCAUUUCUUUAUCAAGACGCCAAGAACCUGGACACCCUCCACCGGUAACAGGAGGAGCAUUAGUCAGCCUACCACAGACUCCAACGAACGUUUUUUGAGAGGAAAUGAAAGAAUAUUCCUAAGUUAUUGGGUGCCUUUUCUUCAGGAAUCCCUGAAAGUGGGGGUUUGCAAUUUUCCCUGGAUUGAAAACAGAAAUGCUUCCUACACAAACAUGAUUGAGACCUUGUACUCUAGGUGUAAAAAAACAGAGUAGGUCAUACUCUGUGGGUUAUGGUCAGAGAGAUCUGGUUAGAAGUUCCCAGGUAGGCGACAGCCCUAGAUGUGUGACACUUCUAGGAGAAUCUCUGGCUAUGUGGAUACGUCCAGGUGUGUAAGGCAGCCUCAGGGACUGCCACCACUUGGUCACAUACAUGUCCCUCCAACUAAUCCUAGCUCUCAAGGACAGGUGGUUCUGGGCCCUGUGUUGCCCAUGAGACUUGGUCCACGGCAAGCCUGUGACGGAGUGAAAGUGAGGGGACACCCAAUUUGAAAACUCGGCAGGAAGCCAGACUCCAUGACAUACAAAUAGAUCAAAGUGAAUCGGCUCCGUUGUUUGGGGAAAUACCUGAGGUUUGUUGUUUCGUGCCAAGAAGAUUAACAACACGGACACACGUGGGUGGGUUAAGGAGCAGAAAGUUUAACAGGCAGAAAAAAGAGAACAGCUCCCCCAUGCAGAGGGAGGAGGACUCCGAAUGGAUCUCCCCAUUCCUGGCGGGAAGCAGACUGAUAUAUAGAGGAGGGGGUUUGAAGAGGUGGUAUUUGAUUUACAUAGAGCCCAAGGGAUUGGUUUGACCAGGUGUGCCAUUUACAUAGCCCUCGAAGAAACUGGCCAUUCCACCUUGAUCUUUUAUUAUGCAGAUAGGGUUUUUUACUUGGCCAGAGCCUUGACACCUGCACACAUGGCAACAAACAGAAGGGAGGCGAAAUCUUCCAUAUUGGAUGCACCUGUCUUCCAGGUGCAGCUGCCGGCAUUUAUCUGUGCAAGCUUCUAGCUUGCUUAUUUAUGCUUGCAGCUUGACUUUUCAGGCUGCUUUCUGUUGGAAAAGAAAUGGUUUUGGGGGCUGCUUUUUAUUAAAAGAAAAGCCUUACCAAGGACUCCUGUACCCUAUCUGCCUAAAUUUUUUUUAACUACUAUAUUAAAAGGUCUGUAAGUGGGAGCUGGCCCUAAAAGUAGGUUGUAGAGAUUAUUUGGAUGUGCCAACAAGCUUCAUCUGCAGCUUGGACUGUCUCCAUUGGAAGGCCUCUGGCAGAUUUUGUAAAAAGUUAUAUAACAAUUUUACUAUAGGAAAAACUUGGCUACAGAUAUGAAUUUAUAUUACCCAUCAUUGGCUGGUUCCUUAUCCUGAACAUUGGUUUCCUUGGAAUCUGAUUUUGGCUUGUUUGGCCUUUAAAAACCCCAGAAGAAUGGGGUUUCUGCCAGAUUAUUUUCUGGUUUUCAGUCUCACUGAAUGUCACAAAGGCCUUGGUUUAUGGUUCCCAACUGGUAAAGAAACGUCAAACUUUGCCUCUCUUAGUUCCUUCUACAUGACAAUGGGUGGCAGUUGCUCAUAUGGAAGCAUUUCUUUUCCCCCUAAAGCCUAUGAGACAGGCUGCAACUUAAACCCCUAUUUUAUUAAAGGAGAGGAAAUGUCCAAGAGCCCAGAGAUAGUGGGUAAAAGCAUCAUAAGGACUAGAAAUGGGGUCUUCUUGUUGCUAAUUAGUAGGGGUGAGGGGUAAGUGGCAGAUGUGACUGCCGUCCAUGCCCAGACAGGGAAUUGUCCUUGAACCUACUCAUGCGGUGUCUUCUGGGGUACAGUGAGUCCACAGGGCAGGACGGCCUUGGAGUCAAGAGCCCAGACUCACAUUCUAUCUCAGGCUUCAUAACUCAAUUGCUCCAUGACCUUAAGCCAAUUUAGUUCCCUCAUCUGUAAAAAUGGGGAUAACAACUGAAUUUACCUCAUGGGAUUGUGUAAUGCCCAACCUUGUUUUUACUAACCCUGUUUUUAGACUCUCCCUCUUCCUUUAAUCACCUAGCCUUGUUUCCACCUGAAUUGACUCUCCCUUAGCUAAGACAGCCAGACAGACUCCAUCUUGGCUCUUUCACUGGCACCCCUUCCUCAAGGACUUAACUUGUGCAAGCUGACUCCCAGCACAUCCAAGAAUGCAAUUAACUGAUAAGAUACUGUGGCAAGCUAUAUCCGCAAUUCCCAGGAAUUCGUCUGAUUGAUAACGCCCAAAGCCCCGGGUCUAUCACCUUGUAAUAGUCUUAAAGCCCCUGCACCUGGAACUGUUUACUUUCCUGUAACCAUUUAUCCUUUUAACUUUUUGCCUACUUUAUUUCUGUAAAAUUGUUUUAACUAGACCCCCCCCUCCCCUUUCUAAACCAAAGUAUAAAAGAAAAUCUAGCCCUUUCCUCAGGGCUGAGAAAAUUUUGAGUGUUAGCCGUCUCUCGGUCGCUGGCUAAUAAAGGACUCUUAAUUCGUCUUAAA